AAAGAUUCAGAAAAGUGGGCUACUGUGUUCCAGGGUGAGCUUUGAGCUUGGUGCCUUUGGAUGGGUAGGAAUUAAAGAAGCAGAGGGAAUGAGAGGAAGAGAGAAGGAGUUCUCAACAGGGAAGGCAAUGCAGGAUCACAGCAGUGCACACUGAUCACAGACAGAUCUGGAUUUGAAUUCCUGCUGCACCACUUACGAGCUUGGCCAAAUCAAUUAACCUCGUUGGCUCUCCUCUUUGUUGCCAAACAGGGAUGAUCCUAACAUCUGUAGCCACUUCAUGAGUGCUUAUGAUGCAUCUCACUCUGUAUUAGGUAUUUUAUAUAUAUUAUUUAAUUAACACUCUUACAUUUUUACAGAUAAAGAAAUGGAGGCACAGAGAAGUGACUUAUUUAAAGCCUUUGUUUCAGCUAUCAGUUGCUGUGUAACAAACUACCUCGAAACUCUGUGACUUAGAACAACCACAAUUUUCUGUGCUCGUGAUUCUGUGGGUCAGCAAUUUGGGCAGGGUUCAACUGGGGCCACUCCUGUGGCUGCAGUUUUCUGGUCAAUUAAAAAAAGAAAAAGAGCCCAAAGUGAGCAAAUCCCAAUGUGCAAGCACUUUUCAAGCUUCUGCUUGUGUCAUAUUUGCUAAUAUCCCAUUGGCCAAAGCAAGUUACACAGCCAAGCCCAGAGUCCUGGGUUAGAAAAGCAAGGCCCCCUCCCCUUACAGAGUCACAAUGCAAAGGGCCAUGCCUGCAGCCAUGCCAGUAAUGAUCACAAUCCUCUUUGCAAACAGUUCACUCCAGCCACCCAGCUGCUGGCGGCACUAUGUGCCCCAAAUUCAUGCUUCAUUGCUAGGGAUUUCUUUUGAGCACUUUCUAGUUACCAUGCCUGGUUAUACAAGUCUACAGUCCCCCUCCUCCCUCAGCCCUAGGGUCAUUACCACAGUCACUGAGGAACAAAUAAUGCAGAGAAAGGAUUUUCCAGUAAACUCCACUUUUUUUCUUCUUAAAGUUCUGUAAGGGAGGUGGUGGUGGUCUGUUCCGGGGGUCCUACAGGGUAUAAUGAUGGUGGAGAUAAAUGCUAAAGGCCACCCAUCACUUGCUUUAGAGAAAAGGCUUGUCUCUAUCUGGGGCUAGGAAGGAUGCAGAGGAGACUGCAAGGCCAGGCAUUUUGUUCAUUCAUUUAUUCAUUCACUCACUCAAUAAGCCUAGUCCUUAUCACCCAGUCCUUAUCUGCUCAGCCCUUAGCACCUUGAGGCACCCUCCUCUUUAAAACAUGCUAGCAUGGGUGUUUAUGCACAUAUGUGCGCGCGCACACACACACACACACUUGCAUACAUGCAUGUGCAGUUUGACAUGCACCACACACUAGCACAUAUGCACAUUCACGUGCUUGUAUGUACAUACACAUAUAUGCAAGCGUGCGCACACAUAUAUCCCACUCCACUUCUUUUCCCUCGAACUCCCAUCAGCCCAACACAAUAUAGUUCUUGUUCAUGUAUUGGCCUGGGAGAAAAAAAGGGCAGAGGUAAAGAACGUGGACCAGUAUGGCAAUCCUUCUAGAAGAGGCAAAUCAAAACAAAACAACUCACAAACUGUAAGCCCCACUGUGUUUUCACUGUUCGGCUAAAAAUGUGUUCAGAUUUUCAAUAUAUUUCUAUAUUAUGAAAUGCAUGUGUGUCAGUAACUAGUGAACGUCCAGUGUCCCCCCACCUGUCUCUUCCUCUGUGUUCAGCAGCUCUGCUCCAAACUGUGGGCUGGCCUUCCAAGCCCAGGGCUGCAGGAGAGGCCCAGUGACUUUGUUCUUUGCCAUGUGGGGAGGGCCUGAGGAGUGUCCAUUCAUACCCAGUAGCAGCUGGUCACAGGUAGACCCUAACUGGAGCCAUGAAUCACUCUACCUUUGACUUGUUCAAGCCUUGAUUGAUUGUGUAUGGGCUCAGGGAUGUGACAUCAACUCUGGGCCAACAGGCAAAUCUUGGCAAAGGUGUCUCCCUCCUCAUGACUUCCCUCAGAGAUGGGGAUGGUGGAGAGAGCUGAGACUGGGAGCCCAGGAGCCUGAGUUCUGGUCCCAGCUCCACCCUGGGCUCACUGCGUGUCUUUCUAGGAUGACAUUCAGGUACAGCCCCACAGCUUCAUCCUAUCUUUGGGCCCUCUGUCAUUUACUGAAUAUUUUUCUUUAAGUUGACCUCCCCUCCCUUUUUAAGUUCCCCCAGUGUUAGUUAAUUAGUGGAAAGCAGCCCUGCGUGCUGGAAGAGCACAGGUUUUAGAGUCAGCUGGACCUAACUUGAAGGCCCUGCCACACAAACUCCCUGAGCCCAGUCCCUCCCUGGAACAUGGGGCUGCUGCCAGUUCAUUUGUCUGGAUUAUUCUGGGGAGAGUGAUUGUCAUAGAGUAUAGCCCAGUGCCUAGCAAACCUGAGUCCUGAGUCAUUGUGUCUUUUAUGAAAGAAUGAGGCAUAAAUAUUUUUCCUACAUAGUUUGGAAUCUUUCUUCUCCAUUCCCCAUCUCCACUGGGCCAGCCAGAGCCCUAAGAAUGUUUCGCUGGAAAACGUGCAGCCACCUCCUCCUUCGUUUCCCAUUCUCCGGGCCUGCUCUCUGUGAUGCUGGCUCCAUACUUGAGCUGGAUGACUUUCCUUUAAAAAAAUUGUUUAAUAUUUAAAUUUAGAAAUAGAAGAUACAUACACUUGGUUAAAAAAAUAAGACAGUAAUUAAACAAUAAAAGAAGGUACCCAGGAAGAAGCAUGUCUCCUGACUCUUUCUCCAUCCCCGUAUAAUCUCAGUUACUAGGUUAUUAGUGUCCAGUUAGCCAUGUCUCCUUCCAGAGACCUUUUAGCCAUCAAUCAGCACACACGUUUGGGCAUAUCCCACACAUUCCUGUUUUAUGCAAGUGGUGACAACUGUACUUACUAUUCUGCAUCUUGCUUUGCGUUCAUAGGUAUAUUUUGGAGAUUGUUUCAUCUCAAGAAUAACUAGAGCCUCCAAUCAUGUACAGUGCUUGUUGAAGGCCAGGGGCUGGUCUAAAUGCUUUACAUGUACCGAUCCAUUUCAUCCUCAUCGUAACCCUUUGAGGUCAUGAAAACCUACCACAUGUACCAUGCAGAGAGCAUCAGUGCGGAAAGCAAGCUGAAGGAGGCUGAGAAGCAGGAGGAGAAGCAGUUCAAUAAGUCAGGAGACCUCAGCAUGAACCUGCUCCGGCACGAGGACCGGCCCCAGCGCCGCAGCUCUGUGAAGAAGAUUGAGAAGAUGAAGGAGAAGAGGCAGGCCAAGUACUCUGAGAACAAGCUGAAAUGCACAAAGGCCCGGAAUGACUACUUGCUCAAUCUGGCAGCCACCAACGCAGCUAUAAGCAAAUACUACAUCCAUGAUGUCUCUGAUCUGAUCGAUUGCUGUGAUUUGGGCUUCCAUGCCAGCCUGGCCCGCACCUUCCGGACCUAUCUCUCAGCUGAAUACAACCUGGAGACCUCUCGCCACGAAGGGCUGGAUGUCAUUGAGAAUGCAGUGGACAACCUGGAUUCCCGAAGUGACAAGCACACAGUCAUGGACAUGUGCAAUCAAGUCUUCUGCCCUCCACUCAAGUUCGAGUUCCAGCCCCACAUGGGGGAUGAGGUCUGCCAGGUCAGCGCUCAGCAGCCCGUCCAGACAGAACUGCUCAUGCGUUAUCACCAGCUGCAGUCCAGACUGGCCACCCUCAAGAUAGAGAAUGAGGAGGUUAGGAAAACCCUGGAUGCCACCAUGCAGACAUUACAGGACAUGCUGACUGUGGAGGACUUUGAUGUCUCCGAUGCCUUCCAACACAGUCGAUCGACAGAGUCCGUCAAGUCGGCUGCCUCUGAGACCUACAUGAGCAAGAUCAACAUUGCCAAGAGGAGAGCCAACCAGCAGGAAACAGAAAUGUUUUAUUUUACAAAAUUUAAAGAGUAUGUGAAUGGCAGUAACCUCAUCACCAAGCUGCAGGCCAAGCACGAUUUACUCAAGCAGACCCUGGGCGAAGGGGAAAGAGCAGAAUGCGGCACCACCAGCAGAAGAGAUGGAAGGCUUAGGCUGCCCCACUUUCCUUGGCCGAGCUGCCCCCCUGCUCCCCACUUUGUGCCCCACCCAGCACUUCAAGGAAGAAGAAAUGCUCGAACCAGGAACCAGGAUUCAGGACAAGCUAUACCGCUUGUAGUCGAGAGCUGCAUCCGUUACAUCAAUUUAUAUGGACUCCAGCAGCAGGGGAUCUUCAGAGUGCCAGGAUCUCAGGUGGAAGUCAAUGACAUCAAAAAUUCCUUUGAGAGAGGUGAAGACCCCCUUGUGGACGAUCAAAAUGAACGAGAUAUCAAUUCAGUCGCUGGUGUUUUAAAACUGUAUUUCCGAGGACUGGAAAACCCACUCUUUCCUAAGGAAAGGUUUCAAGAUUUGAUAUCUACUAUUAAACUGGAGAACCCAGCCGAGAGGGUGCACCAGAUCCAACAAAUCCUCGUCACCCUUCCCCGCGUGGUCAUUGUGGUCAUGAGAUACCUCUUCGCUUUCCUCAACCACCUCUCCCAGUAUAGCGACGAGAACAUGAUGGAUCCCUACAACCUGGCCAUCUGCUUCGGGCCUACCCUCAUGCACAUCCCUGAUGGGCAGGACCCUGUGUCCUGCCAGGCACACAUCAAUGAAGUCAUCAAAACCAUCAUCAUCCAUCAUGAAGCCAUCUUCCCCAGCCCCCGGGAGCUAGAGGGACCUGUGUAUGAAAAAUGCAUGGCUGGAGGGGAAGAAUAUUGUGACAGCCCACACAGCGAGCCAGGGGCCAUCGAUGAAGUUGACCAUGACAAUGGCACUGAGCCUCAUACCAGCGAUGAAGAAGUGGAGCAGAUCGAGGCUAUUGCCAAGUUUGACUACAUGGGGCGGUCCCCGCGUGAGCUAUCCUUCAAGAAGGGGGCCUCGCUGCUCCUGUACCACCGCGCCUCGGAGGACUGGUGGGAGGGCCGGCACAACGGCGUGGAUGGACUCAUCCCCCAUCAGUACAUAGUUGUACAGGACAUGGAUGAUGCCUUCUCCGACAGCCUGAGCCAGAAGGCUGACAGCGAGGCCAGCAGUGGGCCAUUGCUGGAUGACAAGGCCUCUUCCAAAAACGACCUCCAGUCCCCCACGGAGCACAUCUCGGAUUACGGCUUUGGGGGGGUGAUGGGCCGAGUGCGGUUACGAUCUGAUGGAGCAGCCAUCCCCAGACGCCGAAGCGGGGGCGACACACACAGCCCGCCCCGGGGCCUGGGCCCCAGCAUAGACACACCACCCCGGGCUGCUGCCUGCCCCAGCAGCCCCCACAAAAUCCCCCUCACCCGGGGGAGGAUCGAGAGCCCUGAGAAGCGGAGGAUGGCGACGUUCGGGAGCGCUGGCAGCAUCAACUACCCUGACAAGAAGGCGCUCUCCGAAGGGCACUCGAUGAGGUCGACCUGCGGUUCCACCAGGCACAGCAGCCUAGGGGACCACAAGUCCCUGGAGGCCGAGGCCCUGGCAGAAGACAUCGAGAAGACCAUGAGCACGGCUCUGCACGAGUUGCGGGAACUCGAGAGGCAGAACACGGUCAAGCAGGCGCCAGAUGUGGUGCUGGACACCCUGGAGCCCCUGAAGAACCCGCCAGGCCCCGUCAGCUCGGAGCCCGCCAGUCCCCUUCACACCAUCGUCAUCCGCGACCCCGAUGCCGCCAUGCGCCGCAGCAGCAGCUCCUCCACCGAGAUGAUGACCACCUUCAAGCCAGCCCUGUCCGCCCGCCUGGCUGGCGCCCAGCUCCGCCCGCCCCCCAUGCGGCCCGUGCGGCCGGUGGUCCAGCACCGGUCCAGCAGCAGCAGCAGCUCGGGCGUGGGCAGCCCGGCCGUGACGCCCACCGAGAAGAUGUUCCCCAACAGCUCAGCGGACAAGUCGGGCACCAUGUGACCUGCAGGAUGGGCCGCGCCGCCGUGGCCCGCUGUGGCUCACCACGGCCCAGGGUGGCCUUGGUGGCUUCCACGUGCUUCCCAGUGACCCUGGCCUUGGAGGGCAGAGGUCCGUCUGGGAGGGUGUGUCUGUGCAGAGCUGAGGCCCGGGCGCUGGCUGCAGCUCACGUCCAGCCAUGGGAAUCCCACGGACCUCUCGCGUGUCAACAGACGACCAGAGGAGUGCUGGAGCUCCAGCAGCCCCAACCACAGCAUUCCCUAACAUGGAGGCAAAAUACCACAUGGCUUCUCCCGCAUAUCGUCACUGGAAACUUCCUCUCUCGACAUUCUCUCUACAUACGUAUAUGUGUGUGUAUAUCGAUGUGUGCAUAUAUACACAUGUAUACGUAUGUACGUGUCUGUAGGUGUGUGUAUAUAUAUAUAUAUUUAUGCAUCUAUAUACAUAUACUAGAUCUGGACACACGCAUACUAAGUGUAUAUAGUAUCUCCUUUUUCUUUUUAUGAAACUUAGAUUUACCUCAGAUCCAUGCCACCAAACAUCUCCCACCGAGUUAUUUGGUGGGAUUUGCAGGGACUUUUCUGGGAGAACUUAAAGGCCCAUAGUAACUGCGAAUGAAGCAAUAUACCACUAACCUGCAGAAAAACACAAACAAAAACAGACUCCCACUGUCUCCAGAAGUCGUGGCCUUCCAGAACAGUCUGCCCCUCAAGGAAGGGUGGGGCAGGCAGUACCCCCAAGCAGGCUGCUCCCAGAGGUGGGGAACCCUUCAUAGGAAAUCCCCACCCCCGUCCACCCCAGAGACCCUGCCCUUCCACCCGGAGGCCAAAGGCCAACUGUACUCCCAAAGGCAUGGGAGAAGGUUGGCGAGAAGACCCCUGACUACCACAUCCUUGUGUUUGUGUGUAGAGACGGGGGAUAGUGAGAACCUAAGCCCCAUCGUAGCACAGUAUUACAUGUGGUUGGGAAAAAUAAAAAUACAGUGGUGUGGAAUACUCCAAAACCUAGAAAUGCUGUAGGAAUAAAUCUGUGGUAACUAUAGAGGUUUAACUUAUAUCAUUUUCAAACUAUUUAAUUUUUUCUUUUCCUGGUUCUACUAAUUAUACUGUGUCAGAUUUGGAACUAAACAGGCAAGGAGGCUUUGAGUCACAUCGUUUUCAUUUUAAAUCAGGCUGUGAUGCACUGUGGCUGGUGCCGUCUUGCAUGAAACGCAUGAGCCGUGAGCGCCCAGUUCAGACUGGGGCCAGGGAGGGGCAGUCCUUGGCACUUUCUGUCCUAGAGGACACUGUCAGUUGAGUUAAUACAAGUGACAUAGCUUCCCUUCCCUCCCCCUUCACCCACUCCCUCCAGAACAUUUAGUGUAGAUGAAAAUGUGGUGAUAGAAAUGGGUGCAUGAUCUUCACGUGUGACAGCCAGGCCUUUGCCUCUUGGCCAAGUAAAGCCCUUCCGGGUCGCUCUCCUUCGAUUCCAUUUUACCUCCUCUUCUGAUCACUUCCAGAGAUGAGCUGUUUCUGGAUAAUGGCACACGGGCAAAUCUGUGUGCCCUGUGGGCCGCUGUUACUUACCCUCUCCUGCGAGACCCAGGGGCUUUUCCCUACUGUUCCCACGCUUCCUCUCUCUCGAGGCCACUGAAGUUUGGAGUCAAAAGGCCCAGAGUCUGAGUCCCAGCCCUGAGCACUUAGGAGCCUUCUGACUUAGGGUUUGUCACUCCACCUCAUUGAGCCUGACUGUUCUGCUCCAUAAAAUAGGGUAAUAAAGGUCAAACAUCAGUGAGCAAGCUGUGUACACUGGAAAACACUGAAUCAAUACAAUGCGUUUGUGAUUAUCAUUAGUAAGGUAAGUCUUAGAUCAGAGCCCUCCAGCCCUUCUUUUUGAAACCUCCCAAUGGCAUUUCAGAAGUGAGCAGUGGAAUUUUCCUGCCAUCCUAAUAAGAGCCCUGGAUUCCAUCAUUAACAUUUCAGCCCAUUGGAUGAAGUGGUGCCCUCUCCUCUGGUCCCCCGCGAAAAGGUAAAUACACCCAAAGGGAGGGACCUAGUUAAGUCACUGGCACCUAGAUAAGUUAGGAGGGUAAAGCCACUACCUCGUCUGAAGGACUGGACUUGACACCCCACAGUGGAAGGGAGCAUCAGGAGAGGAACAAAAAAAGGGAUCUCAGGGAGAGGCCAGUGUCAAACUUGACCUCCCUUGUUUGGCCUAGAAUGAACCCUUCUCUUUAGCUCCUGGAUAUGAAAGGCCAUCUGCUUGGAGCACAGAAAGAUAUUGCCAUUUUACAGCUUAAGAGAGUAAGGCCUUGGGCUGUGCUGUGACCUGCCCAAGAUUUGACACUGGCUAGGAGCAGAGGCUGCGUCAGGCUCUUAAAGUCAUGUGUUUGCAUGCUGGAUGCUAUACUGUCCAGCCAGGACACAAGACUUCUGAUUUCUACCCUCAAGAUACUCCCAGAUCCUAAAUCCAGUAGCCUCCCAGGCAAAAUAUAGCAAUCUGCCACAACUGCCAGAUGAAAAGCAACAAUCAGAGUAGAAAAAUCUGUUGCCUGAUAUACAUAACACCAAUCAGACCGUGUGGAUUUUUCUCUGAAUUGACUGAUUUUGUUUUUUUCUUACUGAAAAUGGACCUGCCUUUCACUGAAUUUUCUGAGGGCAGAGUCUUAGCUGUUUUCUUUAAGCACCUUUUUUUUUUUUUUCCAUUGGGAAAUGGCUGAUGAGUUCACAUUUAGGGAUGUACACACACAGAUGGCAGACGUCUCCCCACUCAUCCAGCCCCAGAUCUGAGCCUUGACGCAGGCCAAGUGGAAAAAUACUUUCCCGCCCCCCUCCCCUGUUCCCACUUCCUCAUCUGGCACUAUGCAUGUCUCACUCACCCUCCACAGCACUCAGUCCCAUCGACGUUCACUGAACAUUGGCUUUCUCUUUCUGACUCCUGCCUGUUUUAGUCCACUAUAUAUUGCUGUAUUUGCUUAAAUGCUGGAAAGUAACUGUUAAAAUGUGAAAUUGUAAUUUUUAAAAAGGCUACAAUUAAAUUUUAGCCAAUGCCACUCACCAAAUCUUUGCACCUAGUAGAUAGAUCAAUGUAAAAACAAAUACCUAACUGUACAGUGAGUGUGGGGGAAAUGUAGUAACCUAGUUAGUAGUCUUCAAUAUAACCAAUUGUACAAGGGGAAGUGGUGUUUACCUACUUGUUCAUCACCAUUAUUGAAAGCCGUACUGAUCAGUUAGUUGACAACGGGCAUUUUUUUUUCUUUGCUUCAUGGAAUGAUUUCUUUUCUUAACCUUCGACUUAUCCUGAGGUCAAGCCUUUUGUCUUUAUGUGUAACCGACGUUCAGUCUAUUCUAGGAAUGAACCAGCAAGUUGUUCAUUUAAAACUGACCAAAGACAAUUAAUUCCUGGUCUAGUUUCCUGGGCCUUGUGGCUCAGCUGCCACUAAAGAGCUUUUUGGAUAAAAUUGAGAACAAGCUGUGCUUCCUACCCCACUCUCCCCGUCCCCUUUUAUUCCCUUUUCCUCUUAAAGAGCUGCUCUGAGCUGUGGGAUUCUAUGAAAAAUUCUUGCCUUUCCUUGUUUCAGUGCUAACGAUUUCUCACCUCGAAGCGCCUUUUGAACCCCGGACAGAGUGCACAAUCGGAGGGAAUUGCGAGCUUGGGAAUUAGACUUUGGAGUCUUUUCUCUGAAGUCACCAGGCCAGGGGUCAGGAGAGAGAUGGAUUCCCAAGGGAUGAAAGGUUUCUAUUCAAUGAAGAAAUCGGAGUGGGAAGAGACACAGGGAAAUUGAGCCAUAUUUUGGCUAUCGGCUGGAACCAGCAGUUCAGAGAUCUGCCUUAUAAACAUUUAAAACCGGUUUGUGGUACACAAAGAGGAACCAGUGUGGGAAGGGGCCUUUAUGUGGGGCUUUCUUCUCUGUUGGAGUCCCUUGGAGUGCCUUGUUGGGUAUAUUUCUCUGUCAUUCAGGAGGCACGAAUGUGGAGGACUUCUCGUGACCUGGUCGUGAUGUGGCAUUCAGUGCAUGUCCACAGCUAAUGGAAAAACACGAGGACUCGGGUAAUGGUUCUUCCUCUCAGUCUUUCUAUUCCUAACUUUUCACACAUCCAGAUGGUUCCACACUAGUGCAAAUGCCUCACUCUCCUGAGAAACCCAGAAAGAAGAGUGGCUGGCUCACAACCAUGGGGUUAGCCCCUGCUGGGCUGGGAGUCGGGGUGGCGGCCAGGAGGAAAGGCAGAAAGGGGUGAGCCGAGGUGUUGCCUAGCUGAUUUUCUGCUGUGCAGAGCUAAUGCUGACAUUUCAUGUCAACUUCCCCGGUUCUCUGGGGUCUCCUCUCCUCUGAGCAGCCACAUAGAACAUUCCCCACAUAUCCAAAGCUGCCCAGGGGAGCCGAGAGAAGGGACUUUGCUGUCAGGUCCAAGCCCUCCUGACCUCCCUGAGAUUGAUCUGCCAGUGUCCUGCUGUCCCUCUGGGACUGGCCACAUGGCCAUCGCUGCCCCUUGUUGACACCUCCUUUCUGUGUGAGUUGUCCCCGGCCAAUAACAAAGCUGUUCCUUGAACCAGAACAACCAGAGUGCACUUUUCCUUCCUUAGACGGAAGUAGAUCCUGGCUAGGGUUUCUGCCCAGGCCCUUGUUCCCGGCAGUGUGACUGUUUACAUGGUUUGGCAAUAGGUUUGAUUCUGAUUGCUUCAGAGUGGCUGGUCUAUUUUGUUUCCUUUGGUUUCCUUCCUCCCCAAAUUGUGACAGGAAAAACAGACCAAAACCACCCUAGGAAAUUGCUGGUUGCCUGUCCCCACGUGAUGAUAAAUGUUGCCCUCUUCUGGAUAUCGUUUCUCUACCUUACGACCAAACGCCCGUCCUAUAGAGUGUCUGAUUGGAUCCUCUGUCGCGUAUUCUGAUGGUGCCUGCUGGUUUGACGUGGAGCUAUCCUGUGAAAUAAAACAGCUUAACUUUUCUCAAA